CUCUUCCGUCGCAGAGUUUCGCCAUGGUAAGACCGAUAGUUCCUAACUCCUAGUAUAUCUGCCUCCAUCAUUUGAAAAAGGGCCGUUCUACCUUGGCGAUGUUUCACUUUUCGGUCGCCCCUACUUGGUGGGUGGGAAUGCUGCUGGUGCUGCUUCAGGAAACCCGAUUUGGAGAGGGGAGGUCUGAGAAGAGUGUGUCUCGUUGUGCUCGGUCUGGGGGCCGUCACGUGAGUCCAUCCUUGACGCAGCCCGGCAGUGGCUUUUUACCCGGAUUAGCUUAUUUUCACACGUUGAAGCAGCCUCAGAUUCGCUUGGAGAGCACUGUGGACGCUCUCUUGACGGAUGCUAGGGAGACCCGCCAAGUUUUCAAAGGCCCGGGGCCCCAAGAAGCACUUAAAGCGUGUUGCAGCGCCGAAGCAUUGGAUGCUUGACAAACUAACGGGUGUAUUUGCACCUCGUCCAUCGACAGGUCCCCACAAGCUGAGGGAAUGUCUUCCUCUGAUCGUCUUCCUCAGGAAUAGACUCAAGUAUGCGUUGACUGGAGAUGAGGUAAAGAAGAUAUGUAUGCAACGUUUCAUCAAAAUUGAUGGCAAGGUUCGAGUGGAUGUCACAUACCCUGCUGGAUUCAUGGAUGUCAUCAGCAUCGAGAAGACAGGUGAACAUUUCCGCCUGGUCUAUGACACCAAGGGCCGUUUUGCUGUUCACCGCAUCACAGUGGAAGAGGCAAAGUACAAGUUGUGCAAAGUGAGGAAGAUUACUGUGGGAGUGAAGGGAAUCCCUCACCUGGUGACUCAUGAUGCUCGAACCAUCCGCUACCCAGAUCCUGUCAUCAAGGUGAACGAUACUGUGCAGAUUGAUUUAGGGACUGGCAAGAUAAUCAACUUUAUCAAAUUUGAUACAGGCAAUUUGUGUAUGGUGAUUGGUGGAGCCAACCUCGGUCGUGUUGGUGUGAUCACCAACAGGGAAAGACAUCCUGGUUCUUUUGAUGUGGUGCAUGUGAAGGAUGCCAAUGGCAACAGCUUUGCCACGAGGCUUUCCAACAUUUUUGUCAUUGGCAAUGGCAAUAAACCUUGGAUUUCCCUGCCCAGGGGAAAGGGCAUUCGACUUACUGUUGCUGAAGAGAGAGAUAAGAGGCUGGCCACCAAACAGAGCAGUGGCUAAAUUGCAGUAGCAGCAUAUCUUUUUUUCUUUGCACAAAUAAACAGUGAAUUCUCGUUUCUUAAUGUGUUUUUUCCCCCUUGUGGAUAAUAGUAGGGUUUGAAUUUGCUCAUGAUUUUGGCACUGUCUUAAGAUCUCUAGGAAUACCACCUAUACUUCCUCUGACCCUCCAGUAAAUAAACCUUUGCUUCCCUCAUACAUGUUACCCACACCAUCUCUGUGGGCAGAGUGAUGGAGUAGCAUUCCAAAACGAAGUACAAAAAACGUAUGACAUUUCAGAAAGGACGGCAUUCUUUUGUGGAAGCUAUGGGAGAUGGUCUUAGUUUUCUUGCUUGUUCACAUUAUUGGUAGAAAUUAAAUCCUGUGGCUGUAGGAAA